CCUCUCCCCUCUCUCUGAGUGGGCGGGGACAGCGGUUGCAUGGGCAGCUUUCCUUAUGAUGCUACAGGUCCCUCUGGACAUGCUGCGCCUGGCCACGCCUCCUUUCCCUUUCAUCUUUCUCACUGACCAAUGGGCUUGGAACAUUAAGGCCACGCCCCUAUUCUGCGUUCCAUUGGUGCCCUGGUUACGCCACCUGUGGCUCAGUUGCACAGCUGCCUGGUAGGUGACUGGAGGCAUUGAGCAGUGCUCACUGGUAUUUCGCUGAUGUGGCCCCAACCCCGCCUCCCUCCCCACCCCGCGAUGUCAGAAAAAACACAACAGGGGAAAUUGGCCGCAGCCAAGAAAAAGUUAAAAGCAUAUUGGCAGAGGAAGAGCCCUGGCAUUCCAGCAGGAGCUAACAGGAAAAAGAAAGUCAAUGGCAGUAGCCCUGACACAGCCACUUCUGGUGGUUACCACUCACCUGGGGAUUCAGCAACAGGUAUCUACGGGGAGGGCCGUGCAUCCUCUACUACCCUGCAGGAUCUGGAGAGCCAGUACCAAGAACUAGCAGUAGCCCUGGAUUCAAGCUCCGCAAUAAUCAGUCAACUCACUGAAAACAUCAAUUCACUGGUUCGCACAUCUAAGGAGGAGAAGAAGCAUGAGAUACAUCUGGUACAGAAGCUUGGGAGGAGCUUGUUCAAACUCAAAAACCAGACGGCUGAACCCCUGGCCCCACAGCCCCCAGCAGGGCCAUCUAAGGUGGAGCAGCUACAAGAUGAGACCAACCACCUAAGGAAGGAGCUAGAGAGUGUGGGAAGACAGCUCCAGGCUGAGGUGGAAAACAAUCAGAUGUUGAGUCUCCUGAACAGGAGACAGGAGGAGAGGCUACGUGAACAGGAGGAGAGGCUACGUGAACAGGAGGAGAGGCUGUGUGAACAGGAGGAGAGGCUGUGUGAACAGGAGGAGAGGCUACGUGAACAGGAGGAGAGGCUGUGUGAACAGGAGAAGCUGCCAGGGCAGGAGAGGCUGCUGGAAGAGGUGGAGAAGCUGUUAAAACAGGAGAGGCGGCAGGAGGAGCAGGAGAGGCUGCUGGAGAGGGAGAGGCUGCUGGACGAGGUGGAGGAGCUCCUGGAGCAGGAGAGGCUUCGGCAACAGGAUGAGAGGCUGUGGCAGCAGGAGACUCUGCGGGAGCUGGAGAGGUUGCGGGAGCUGGAGAGGAUGCUGGAGCUGGGGUGGGAAGCCCUGUACGAGCAGCGGGCCGAGCCACGCAGCGGCUUCGAGGAGCUGAACAACGAGAACAAGAGCACACUGCAGUUGGAGCAGCAAGUAAAGGAGCUGGAGAAGUCGGGUGGAGCUGAAGAGCCAAGAGGCUCCGAGUCUGCAGCAGCAGCCAGACCAGUACCUGGAGCCCCAGUCCCACAAGGAGCUUGGAUGUGCGGACAAGCAGGGUGGACUCCCCAGGAGCACCCAGGCUUGAGUGGAGAAGCUGUUGGUACAGGAGAGGCGGCAGGAGGAGCAGGAGAGGCUGCAUGCCAUUCUUUUCGGGCUGCCGAGAACAGGGAGCUAAACAUCACCAUCAUCUAAGAGCGGGUCAAGAAAUUGAAAAAAAAAAACAAAACAUUUAAGGGGUUAAUAUCCUACACAAUUCAUUUACUUCAUUUGAAUGUUAGAGCCACUUAUGUUUGUGUUUCUAAUUUAUAGUUUAAAUUUAUUUGUGUUUCUAAUUUAUAGUUUAAAUUUAUUUGUUUCUAAUUUAUAGUUUAAAUUUAUUUGUGUUUCUAAUUUAUAGUUUAAAUUUAUUUGUGUUUCUAAUUUAUAAUUUAAAUUUAUUUGUAAAAAGUUAAAUGAGAGUGGGUCUUUCUCUCAUGUUCACUCUGGCAUCUUUUAGCAUUUUUUUAAUUUGAUAAUUAUAGGACGUUAGCAUGCAUAUCGAGUUUGCCCUUAUGUGGUGGGAGUUCAAACACACAAAGACCCACUGUAUGCACACAACUGUUCUUGCUGGUUUGGGAUAGGCUGCCAUGCUUUUUUAAUGUUAGUACAGCCUGUAUAUUCAUUACGGAAUUCAGAUAAAAUUUCCUUAUGUUCUGCUGUUAUGUUUGAUCGAAUCCUAAUCACAGUGAGCUCUUCAUUAGCUCAAUAUGUGGUUUGCCCUCUGGAAACAGCCUUUCCCCCUUUUUCUGUGUAUUGGGGAUGGGAGUAAUAACAUUUUGGGGAGGUUUUUAAAUCUCCCAGAAGAGGAAAGUGGCCUGCUUUGGCAGGUGUGUGCAGGAUAGAAUAUGUUUCAUUUGUUCCGGUGCCAAGAAUGAGCGCUGUACUACGGUAGUUCCCUUAGGAUUUGUAUGUGCUCUAGGCUCAUGAAGAUACUGCCUCAUGAGCUGUGGCAGUUGUACUCUUUUUUGAUGACCUGAAAAGGGAUUAUUUCUGAGGAAUGAAAGGCUCCCAUCAUGACUGUGGAUGUGGAAAACCUUUUCUAGCUGAGAGCAUUUAUAUCUACAAUACAUUUUAAAGUCAGAGUUCAUGUUCCCUGUUUUAAUCACAUGACUACAUGUCCCAGUACACAAAAGGGCACUGGUUGGCGUUCUCCUUAAUGUAUUUAGUAAAGAUCAGAAGAAAUCCUUUAAGAGUUUAAAUGCCCCUGGAACAGGCAUAUACAGGCUCUAGUCAAGAAUGAAUUCGAGUGAAGGAAAGCUGUGUGACACCUGGCAUUCCUCUGUGUUCAUGGAGCUUAUUUGAGGCUAGAAGAUGGAUUUUACCAUCUAGACCUCUCUGGCUAAUAGCUAGUCUUCAACCAUCUGACAUAGGAAUUUACUUCUUUUCCUUGAAUGGAGAACACUUUAAAAAUAAUAACAAACAUUAUUAUAAACUAAUAUAUGUGAGAGUACUUAGUUGAAACAAAAAGGAGUUUUAGUAGACAGUAUUAUACUACAUUUGAAAAUCAAGGAGCAGUUUAUGCAACGUAAAACGUUUACAAACUGCAGCACAAUCUACUGUUCGUGAAUGUCAAAGUGUCAUGAGGAAAGUGUCUAUACAAUCACAGAGUUAUAUUUCCUCACAAAGUUCUUUACAAAGAGUGAAAUAUGUUUUUAUACCUCUCAGUUUCAGUUAGAGGCAUAUUUUGUGUAAUAUUUAUGGCUUAAAAUGGACUAAAGGUCCUGUUCUUGCCUUGUCUGAACUUGCCGCUUUUGCAUUCUUUGAGUUCAGUUUAAAGACAGUUACUUUAAGCCCAUUUUAAACCCUCAGGCUAGAAAUCGUACCACUGUUAAUUAGCCACAUUAUUUGGUCUAACAGUUUAUCAUUCUGAAACUGAGCUUACCUAAUACAUUGAUAAAUUAUUUCAAAGGUAUUUUUAUAGUUCAAAUCGCUUCACUUUUACCCUGACACGUAUAAAUGACUAGGAAUGACCUUCAGAUAGCGUUUAGCAACUGUAACCAAUCUGACAAUAAUGUGUUCAUCAGGUACCUGUGGAUUAAAUCACAUACUGGCAUAUUUAAGCUGAAUGUCAGUCUGAAAAAUAAAUGUACUAUAUUAACUCAAAUACCACUCUCUGUGUAGGUAUUUUGUCAUAUGUUUAAGAAAAAGCUAAAGAGAAUGGAAAUCCUAUGACAAUAACUAUGACAAUAACUAUGACAAGUCUUUCUUCAAAGUGCAUGCAGUCUUUUGCAGUACCUCAUUCAGCCAAGUAUUUGUUCUCUACCUCAUUCAGUAUAAGGCAGCCUUUAAUUUGCUUAGAAGGCAACAUUAGAAGGUUAGAGUUCAGCAGGAACAUAGAAUUUUAAAAUGUGACUUCAACUGAAUAAAUUUGAAUUUCUGUAGGGAGUAAAGAAUCAAAACACCUAUUUAAAGACUGCAAAAUAUGAUAAUUAUUUUUAAAGUAAUUGAUUAAACCUGGUAGGUUUUCCCAAAAUGAAAAACAAUCAGUUCUAAAACCAAAGCUGAUUUUUAGAAAAUGUGAAAAUGUAAAUCAACCCUAUCCAUAAUAGAUUCUCUAAAACUUUAUCUUACAGUCACUUUCAAAUAACUAUUCAAAAAUGUAACUGCUAUAUUAACGUCUUAAAAUAAUUUAAAACAUUUUAAAAUAUGAAUACUGUAGUUUAAAACAAAGAAUCUAGGGGAAGGAAAAGUAGACAAAGAAAUGCCAAUUCCAGUCCAAAGCUGUAUUUGCCAAGUUUUCUUAGAAUGACUUUUACCGAUUUAUGAAUUCUUAUACACAGAAUGCAUAAUGGAAAUACUGAUUUUUGUCUAAAGUGGCAUUAUUGACUGCUGCUGUGAUGCUACUAUAAUGUAAUACAUUAUUAAAUUGUUUCAAGGUGCUGUUUUGCCUAAAAA